AACCGUAACAGCCACCAGACAAGCUUCAGUGGCCGGCCCUUCACAUCCAGACUUGCCUGAGAGGACCCACCUCUGAGUGUCCAGUGGUCAGUUGCCCCAGGAUGGGGACCACAGCCAGAGCAGCCUUGGUCUUGACCUAUUUGGCUGUUGCUUCUGCUGCCUCUGAGGGAGGCUUCACGGCUACAGGACAGAGGCAGCUGAGGCCAGAGCACUUUCAAGAAGUUGGCUACGCAGCUCCCCCCUCCCCACCCCUAUCCCGAAGCCUCCCCAUGGAUCACCCUGACUCCUCUCAGCAUGGCCCUCCCUUUGAGGGACAGAGUGGAAAGGAGGGAAGAGGCCCUCGCCCCCACUCCCAGCCCUGGCUAGGAGAAAGGGUGGGCUGCUCACACAUUCCCCCUUCUAUAGUGCAGCCCCCUCCCUCUCAGGAGGCCACCCCUCUCCAACAGGAAAAGCUGCUACCUGCCCAACUCCCUGCUGAAAAGGAAGUGGGUCCCCCUCUCCCUCAGGAAGCUGUCCCCCUCCAAAAAGAGCUGCCCUCUCUCCAGCACCCCAAUGAACAGAAGGAAGGAACGCCAGCUCCAUUUGGGGACCAGAGCCAUCCAGAACCUGAGUCCUGGAAUGCAGCCCAGCACUGCCAACAGGACCGGUCCCAAGGGGGCUGGGGCCACCGGCUGGAUGGCUUCCCCCCUGGGCGGCCUUCUCCAGACAAUCUGAACCAAAUCUGCCUUCCUAACCGUCAGCAUGUGGUAUAUGGUCCCUGGAACCUACCACAGUCCAGCUACUCCCACCUCACUCGCCAGGGUGAGACCCUCAAUUUCCUGGAGAUUGGAUAUUCCCGCUGCUGCCACUGCCGCAGCCACACAAACCGCCUAGAGUGUGCCAAACUUGUGUGGGAGGAAGCAAUGAGCCGAUUCUGUGAGGCCGAGUUCUCGGUCAAGACCCGACCCCACUGGUGCUGCACGCGGCAGGGGGAGGCUCGGUUCUCCUGCUUCCAGGAGGAAGCUCCCCAGCCACACUACCAGCUCCGGGCCUGCCCCAGCCAUCAGCCUGAUAUUUCCUCGGGUCUUGAGCUGCCUUUCCCUCCUGGGGUGCCCACAUUGGACAAUAUCAAGAACAUCUGCCACCUGAGGCGCUUCCGCUCUGUGCCACGCAACCUGCCAGCUACUGACCCCCUACAAAGGGAGCUGCUGGCACUGAUCCAGCUGGAGAGGGAGUUCCAGCGCUGCUGCCGCCAGGGGAACAAUCACACCUGUACAUGGAAGGCCUGGGAGGAUACCCUUGACAAAUACUGUGACCGGGAGUAUGCUGUGAAGACCCACCACCACUUGUGUUGCCGCCACCCUCCCAGCCCUACUCGGGAUGAGUGCUUUGCCCGUCGGGCUCCUUACCCCAACUAUGACCGGGACAUCUUGACCAUUGACAUCGGUCGAGUCACCCCCAACCUCAUGGGCCACCUCUGUGGAAACCAAAGAGUUCUCACCAAGCAUAAACAUAUUCCUGGGCUGAUCCACAACAUGACUGCCCGCUGCUGUGACCUGCCAUUUCCAGAACAGGCCUGCUGUGCAGAGGAGGAGAAAUUAACCUUCAUCAAUGAUCUGUGUGGUCCCCGACGUAACAUCUGGCGAGACCCUGCCCUCUGCUGUUACCUGAGUCCUGGGGAUGAACAGGUCAACUGCUUCAACAUCAAUUAUCUGAGGAACGUGGCUCUAGUGUCUGGAGACACUGAGAACGCCAAGGGCCAGGGGGAGCAGGGCUCAACUGGAGGAACAAAUAUCAGCUCCACCUCUGAGCCCAAGGAAGAAUGAGUCACCCCAGAGCCCUAGAGGGUCAGAUGGGGGGAACCCCACCCUGCCCCACCCAUCUGAACACUCAUUACACUAAACACCUCUUGGAUUUGGUGUCCUCAUUGUCUAUCUAAUGUCUCACCCGCAGUGUUUUAAGUGGAUCUUGGUGCCCUGGCCCAGGAGGGCACUGGCGUUUUCAGACACACCACAGACAAACACACCCUCCUAAGCCUGCUUGUAUUUCCUUCAGUGCCUGGCCCCUGAGGCCCACGGCCCUGCCCCCUUCACUGAGCAGAUGUUCACAGGCUGUGGGAUGCGACCAUAACUAAACAGCUUGACGUCA